ACAGUAGCCCGGCGGCCCAGGGCAAUCCGACCACAUUUCACUCUCACCGCUGUAGGAAUCCAGAUGCAGGCCAAGUACAGCAGCACGAGGGACAUGCUGGAUGAUGAUGGGGACACCACCAUGAGCCUGCAUUCUCAAGGCUCUGCCACAACUCGGCAUCCAGAGCCCCGGCGCACAGGCUGGAGUAGAGUGGCACGAUCACGACUCACUGCAGCCUUGACCUCCCUGGCUCAAGCAAUCCUCCCACCUCAGCCUUCUGAGUAGCUGCGACUACAGAGCACAGGGCUCCCUCUUCAACGUGGCGACCAGUGGCCCUGACCCUGCUGACUUUGUGCUUGGUGCUGCUGAUAGGGCUGGCAGCCCUGGGGCUUUUGUUUUUUCAGUACUACCAGCUCUCCAAUACUGGUCAAGACACCAUUUCUCAAAUGGAAGAAAGAUUAGGAAAUACGUCCCAAGAGUUGCAAUCUCUUCAAGUCCAGAAUAUAAAGCUUGCAGGAAGUCUGCAGCAUGUGGCUGAAAAACUCUGUCGUGAGCUGUAUAACAAAGCUGGAGCACACAGGUGCAGCCCUUGUACAGAACAAUGGAAAUGGCAUGGAGACAAUUGCUACCAGUUCUAUAAAGACAGCAAAAGUUGGGAGGACUGUAAAUAUUUCUGCCUUAGUGAAAACUCUACCAUGCUGAAGAUAAACAAACAAGAAGACCUGGAAUUUGCCGCGUCUCAGAGCUACUCUGAGUUUUUCUACUCUUAUUGGACAGGGCUUUUGCGCCCUGACAGUGGCAAGGCCUGGCUGUGGAUGGAUGGAACCCCUUUCACUUCUGAACUGUUCCAUAUUAUAAUAGAUGUCACCAGCCCAAGAAGCAGAGACUGUGUGGCCAUCCUUAAUGGGAUGAUCUUCUCAAAGGACUGCAAAGAAUUGAAGCGUUGUGUCUGUGAGAGAAGGGCAGGAAUGGUGAAGCCAGAGAGCCUCCAUGUCCCCCCUGAAACAUUAGGCGAAGGUGACUGAUUCGCCCUCUGCAACUACAAAUAGCAGAGUGAGCCAGGCGGUGCCAAAGCAAGGGCUAGUUGAGACAUUGGGAAAUGGAACAUAAUCAGGAAAGACUAUCUCUCUGACUAGUACAAAAUGGGUUCUCGUGUUUCCUGUUCAGGAUCACCAGCAUUUCUGAGCUUGGGUUUAUGCACGUAUUUAACAGUCACAAGAAGUCUUAUUUACAUGCCACCAACCAACCUCAGAAACCCAUAAUGUCAUCUGCCUUCUUGGCUUAGAGAUAACUUUUAGCUCUCUUUCUUCUCAAUGUCUAAUAUCACCUCCCUGUUUUCAUGUCUUCCUUACACUUGGUGGAAUAAGAAACUUUUUGAAGUAGAGGAAAUACAUUGAGGUAACAUCCUUUUCUCUGACAGUCAAGUAGUCCAUCAGAAAUUGGCAGUCACUUCCCAGAUUGUACCAGCAAAUACACAAGGAAUUCUUUUUGUUUGUUUCAGUUCAUACUAGUCCCUUCCCAAUCCAUCAGUAAAGACCCCAUCUGCCUUGUCCAUGCCGUUUCCCAACAGGGAUGUCACUUGAUAUGAGAAUCUCAAAUCUCAAUGCCUUAUAAGCAUUCCUUCCUGUGUCCAUUAAGACUCUGAUAAUUGUCUCCCCUCCAUAGGAAUUUCUCCCAGGAAAGAAAUAUAUCCCCAUCUCCGUUUCAUAUCAGAACUACCGUCCCCGAUAUUCCCUUCAGAGAGAUUAAAGACCAGAAAAAAGUGAGCCUCUUCAUCUGCACCUGUAAUAGUUUCAGUUCCUAUUUUCUUCCAUUGACCCAUAUUUAUACCUUUCAGGUACUGAAGAUUUAAUAAUAAUAAAUGUAAAUACUGUGAAGUGUGUGUGAUUUUACAAUGGACUUAUGGUUGGUGGGAAAAUUCAGCAUGGAAAUGCUUUUCAAAAUAUGAUAGCGGUCAUUAUUUUGAUUGUGCCUUACUGAAAGUUUUUGGGGAAUUUACAAGAGUACUGAUUACAUGAUUAUCUGGAGAAAAUAAGAUGUCUUUGAAAUACGUGUUGGCUUCAAGAAAACAGUUUUAACGUUUUCCUAAAAUGAAAUCUUUUGAGGUGAGCUUAUGGCAUCAACACAUGGUUGAUGAGGAAGCUGAGUUGCAUUAGUGCACAUGAUUUCCAGUCAGGUCAUGGGAAAUGAACAGAGACAGUGACAUCUUUGUAGCUGCUCCUUUGUGAGGCACUUCUUUCUUGAGACGACUCCAUGCACAAAUAUAACAGGGAUCAUUGGGAAUGACACCAUCACAGCCACCAAGUUUAUUGGUUUACUGAUAAAUCAAUUUUGAGGGUUUUAUGCUAGAAAAGAUAACAUUAUAAAUCUUUGUUUUUCAACAGUGGAAACUGAGGUGCUUCAGUUUUGUUUUUCAUAAACAUCUAUCUCAUGGUAAAAUGACGUAUAGUAGCAAUCAUAUGAUAGAAAGAACACAUUGGUGCUCAUUUUCAUAAACUUCAUUUUGUUAGAUUGUCACUUAGCAAAGACUAUUGCGGAUUCUUCCUUGAGAACUUUCCUUUCAAUUUUCUGUUGAUUUCCUUAAAAUUUUCUUCAGGGUCGAGCAAGUUCUGUUGAUAUAUUGUGUCAUGCAAAGAAAACUGUAUUUGUGGUUAGAAAAUGAAGAUUUUAGACCUCUUAUUCUGAUUUACUUAUUAGGCAAGUCACUUUACUUCAUGAAACCUAUUUCACUGCAUAUGAAGUAGAAAUAAUUAUAAUUUCCUCAUAAUGUUACUGUUAGCUGAAAUAAAGUAAAUGUGAAAUCA